AGAACACAUCUGCUUUCCUGUGUGAGGGUGAGGCUUGGGCCGGGUUCCCCGGGAGGCUCAUCUCCAUUGCGCAGCGCUACGGCGACCCGCAACUCCGAGGCUCGGCUGGAUGUUGAGAGUUGAGGGAGCAGCCGUUUCGGGUGGGCCCAGGCGAGGAGCUGACAGGAAUCGGCGUGGGUCCCGCUCUGGACUACAUUUCCCAGAGGGCCUGGUGGCCUGCCACUUUUCUCGCAGGAAUUCGAACGUUUCGUCACUCCUGGCGGGACCCUUAGAUCUGGGAGGAAACCUCUCUGAGGUCUGGUCAGAUUCCAACCCUGGACAGCAGUGAACACAACCUUUCCCCUGAGCCACUGGAAUUGGACAGAAUGCCCCAUUCUCCUCUGAUCUCCAUUCCUCAUGUGUGGUGUCACCCAGAAGAGGAGGAAAGAAUGCAUGAUGAACUUCUACAAGCAGUAUCCAAGGGGCCGGUGAUGUUCAGGGAUGUUUCCAUAGACUUCUCUCAAGAGGAAUGGGAAUGCCUGGACGCUGAUCAGAUGAAUUUAUACAAAGAAGUGAUGUUGGAGAAUUUCAGCAACCUGGUUUCAGUGGGACUUUCCAAUUCUAAGCCAGCUGUGAUCUCCUUAUUGGAACAAGGAAAAGAGCCCUGGAUGGUUGAUAGAGAGCUGACUAGAGGCCUGUGUUCAGAUCUGGAAUCAAUGUGUGAGACCAAAAUAUUAUCUCUAAAGAAGAGACAUUUCAGUCAAGUAAUAAUUACCCGUGAAGACAUGUCUACUUUUAUUCAGCCCACAUUUCUUAUUCCACCUCAAAAAACUAUGAGUGAAGAGAAACCAUGGGAAUGUAAGAUAUGUGGAAAGACCUUUAAUCAAAACUCACAAUUUAUCCAACAUCAGAGAAUUCAUUUUGGUGAAAAACACUAUGAAUCUAAGGAGUAUGGGAAGUCCUUUAGUCGUGGCUCACUCGUUACUCGACAUCAGAGGAUUCACACUGGUAAAAAACCCUAUGAAUGUAAGGAAUGUGGCAAGGCUUUUAGUUGUAGUUCAUAUUUUUCUCAACAUCAGAGGAUUCACACUGGUGAGAAACCCUAUGAAUGUAAGGAAUGUGGAAAAGCCUUUAAGUAUUGCUCAAACCUUAAUGAUCAUCAGAGAAUUCACACUGGUGAGAAACCCUAUGAAUGUAAAGUAUGUGGAAAAGCCUUUACUAAAAGUUCACAACUUUUUCUACAUCUGAGAAUUCAUACUGGUGAGAAACCUUAUGAAUGUAAAGAAUGUGGGAAAGCCUUUACUCAACACUCAAGGCUUAUUCAGCAUCAGAGAAUGCAUACUGGUGAGAAACCUUAUGAAUGUAAGCAGUGUGGGAAGGCCUUUAAUAGUGCCUCAACACUUACUAACCAUCACAGAAUUCAUGCUGGUGAGAAGCUCUAUGAAUGUGAAGAAUGUAGAAAGGCCUUUAUUCAGAGCUCAGAACUUAUUCAACAUCAGAGAAUCCAUACAGAUGAAAAACCAUAUGAAUGUAAUGAAUGUGGGAAGGCCUUUAAUAAAGGCUCAAAUCUUACUCGACAUCAGAGAAUUCACACUGGUGAGAAACCCUAUGACUGUAAGGAAUGUGGAAAGGCUUUUGGUAGUCGCUCUGACCUCAUUCGCCAUGAGGGAAUUCAUACUGGUUGAAUGACAGUAAAGUAAGACCAUUUUGUUAACCUUUAUAAUAAUUUUUUUAAAACAGGUAAGGAGAACAAAUUAGGAUACAUAUUAUCAAAGGUUCUCCUAUGUAUUCGUUUUUAAACGAUACGAUAACAAAGUACCAAGUACCAAAACCUUGGUGGCUUAAAACAAGAGAAAUUUAUUCUCUCAUAGUUUAGAGCCUGGAAAUCUAAACUCAAGGGUGCUGAUCGUUUUGGUUCCUUCUGAGGACUCUGAGGAUCUGUUCUAUGCCUUUUUCCUAACCUCUGUUAACAGCUGGCAGUCCUUGGCAUUCCAUGGCUUUUACAUACACCAUUCCAAUCUCUGCCUCCAUCUUCACAUUGCAUUCUCGCUGUGUAUCUCUGUGUAUGUCUUUUAUUUGGACACCAGUCAGGUUAGAUUGGGGUUACCUGGUGACCUCAUCUUAACUUGAUUAUAUCUGCCAAGACCCUGUUUCCAAGUAAGGUCACAUUUACCGGUACCAGGGGUUAGGACUUCAGCAUAUCUUUUUAGGGGAUACAGUUCAACCCAUAAUACCCUGUUAGAAUGAUUUUGUCUAAUAUAUUUGUAAUUUCCUUUUAUACAUAAGUUGUUAGUCAAAUUUAUUUUAUUUUAUUUUAUUUUGAGACAGAGUCUCGCUCUGUUGCCCAGGCUGGAGUGCAGUGGUGUGAUCUCAGCUCACUGCAACCUCCAGCUCCUGAGUUCAAGCGAUUCUUGUGCCUCAGCCUCUCAAGUAGUUGGGAUUACAGGCAUGCGCCACCAUGCCCGGCUAAUUUUUUUUUUUUUUUUUUUUGUAUUUUUAGUAGCGACGGGGUUUCACCAUGUUGGCCAGGCUGGUCUUGAACUCCUGACUUCAAGUGAUCUGCCCGCCUCAGCCUCCCAAAGUGCUGGGAUUACAGACGUGAGCCACCGUGAUGGCCAAAACAGACUUUAUACCAACAAAAAUUAAAAAGGACAAAGAAGGUCAUUUAUAAUGAUAAAGGAUAAAUUCAACAAGAAGAUAAAACAAUCCUAAAUAUGUAUGCACCCAACACUGCAACACCCAGAUCCAUAACACAGAUACUACUAGACCUAAGAAAAGAGAUAGACAGCAAUACAACAAUAGCAGGGGACUUCACCACUCCAUUGACAGCACUAGACAGAUCACUGGGACAGAAAUCAACAAAGAAACUCUGGACUUAAAUUGGACUCUACACCAAAUGGACCCAACAGACAUCUGAAGAACAUUCUACCCAACAACCACAGAAUAUAUACUCUUCUCUUCUGUGCAUGGAACAUUCUCAAAAAUAGGUCAUAUACUGGACCACAAAGCAAGUAUCAAUAAAUUUUAAAAAAACAAAAUCAUAUCUAACAUCUUCUCUGACCAUAGUGGAAUAAAACUAGAUAUCAAUACCAAGAGGAACUCUCAAAACAGAUACAUGGAAUUUAAACAGCUUGCUCCUGAAUGAUUUUUGGAUCAAUGAUGAAACUAAGGUGGAAAUUUAAAAUUUUUUGAAAUAAAUGAAAAUAGAGACAAAACACAUGAAAACAUCUGAGAUACAGCAAAAGCAGUGCUAAGAGAGGAUUUUAUAGCAUUAAAUGCCUACACCAAAAAGAUAGAAAAAUCUCAAAUGAAUAGCCUAACGUCACAUCUCAAGGAACUAGGAAAAAACAAAACAAACUCAACCCAAAGCUGGCAGAAGAAAAGCAAUAACAAAUAUCAGAGCAGGCAAAAAUGAGACUGAGAACAAAGGAAUGCAAAAGAUCAAUAAAAGAAAAAGUUGGUUCUUUGCAAAGAUAAAACUGACAGACCACUAGCUAGAUUAACCAAGAAAAAAAGAAGAUUCAAAUAAAUACAAUCAGAAAUGAUAAGGUGAUAUUAUAACUGAUAACACAGACAUAUAAAAUAUCAGCAGAAACUAUAUGCACAUAUUAGAAAACCUAGAGGAAGUGGAUAAAUUCCUAGAAACACAUAACCUUCCAAGAUUGAACCAGGGAGAAAUAGGAAUCCUCAACAGACUACUGAGUAUUGAAAUUGAAUCAGUAAUAGAAAAAAAUCUUGCAAAAACAAAAAGCCCAGGACCAGACAGAUUCACAGCUGAAUUCUACUAGACAUGCAAGGAAGAACUAGUAACAGCACUAUUGAAACUAUUCCAAAAAUUAUAGGAGGGAAUCCUCCCUAACUCAUUCUACAAAGCCAGUAUCAUCCUGAUACUGAAGCCAGGCAAGGAUAAAACACACAAAAAAACUACAAGCCAAUAUCCCUGAUGAAAAUAGACACAAAAAUCUUCAGCAAAAUACUAGCAAACCAAAUCAAACAGUACAUAAAAAAGAUAGUAACAGCACAGUCAAGUGGAUUUUAUUCCUGGGGUGUAAGGAUGGCUCAACAUAUGCAACUCAAUACAUGAUUCAUCACAUACACAGAAUUAAAAAUAAGCCAGGCACUCACACCUGUAAUCCCAGCACUUUGCAAGGCCAAGGCGGGCAGAUCACAUGAUGUCAAGAGUUUGAGACCAGUCUGGCUGACAUGGCGAAACCCUGUCUCUACUAAAAAUAGAAAAAUUGGCUGGGCAUGGUGGCAGGCACUGUAGUCCCAGCUACUUGGGAGGCUGAGGCAGGAGAAUUACUUGAACCUGAGAAGCGGAGGUUGCAGUGAGCUGAGAUAGUGCCAUUGCACUCCAGCCUGGGCAACAGAGCAAAUUGCUUGAAUGUGGGAGGUGGAGGUUGCAGUGAGCCGAGAUUAUGCCAUUGCACUCCAGCCGGGGGAGCAACAAAGCCAGACUCCAUCUCAAAAAAAAACCAAAAAAAAUCCUAUUUAGUACAAGGUACAUUAUUUAGGUAAUGAGUCCAUUAAAAGCCAACACUUUCCCCACUACACUAUAUGUGUAUGUAACACAACUGCCCUUGUAACUUCCUAAACCUAUAAUUAAGAAACAAUAAAAGGCAAAUUAAGAAUGCUUUUUUAAAAGGUGGGGGCAUUAUGCUAAUAAGUUACUGUGGAUUUCAGAGUGCAGAGUAGAAAGAUCACAAGAAUUUAGUGUGGUAGGUGGGAACAGAAAAUGGGUGUAUAAAUUUUAUUGACGUGGGAGUACUGGAUAUUGUAGAGACAGAUAUCAUCAGGGCAAGGAGAUUAAAGAUUUUUGCAUUGACGGUUUGACACUAUAUUGUGGUAAUAACACUGUAUGUGUUGGGAGAUAGAACAGGAAACAUCUUCCCUGGAAUAUGUAUACUAUUAAAUGUUUUAUCAAACUUUUGAUCAAACAAGACAGCACAAUUUAUAAUUUCAUUUCUAUUUCUAUGUUAUGAGAAACUGAUCAUUUAUUCAAAUGUUUAACAGGCAUGUUCAUGUUACUAUAAACUCUUCUGUUUCACCAUCA